CACCCUUUCCAGAUACACACCCGUUUAGUGCGAGAAAUGGAGCGGUUGGGGAGAGGAUCUCCCGAGGGGGCUGGAUUGAGAAUGGGUACCAUUUGAGAUCUCCUAGGAGGCCGGCCAUCGGGCAAUGUCUGAUGGAGUCCAGCCGGUGGAGGAGACUGAAAGGAAACAGCCUGCUUCCUGCAGGUCCGCGGGAGGGAGGUCUUUAAGUGCGUUUGUGCAGCCGAUUUCAAGGCUAAGAGAGAAAGACUGCCUCUGAUCCCUGAAGGAAGAAAAAAAAAAAAAAAACAGGAAAAAAACUCAACAUGGAAAAUGUCCCCAAGGAAAACAAAGUUGUGGAGAAGGCCCCAGUGCAGAAUGAAGCCCCCGCUUUAGGAGGUGGUGAAUACCAGGAGCCUGGAGGAAAUGUUAAAGGGGUUUGGGCUCCACCUGCCCCGGGUUUUGGAGAGGAUGUGCCCAAUAGGCUUGUCGAUAACAUUGAUAUGAUAGAUGGAGAUGGAGAUGAUAUGGAACGGUUCAUGGAGGAGAUGAGAGAGCUAAGGAGGAAAAUUAGGGAACUUCAGUUGAGGUACAGUCUGCGCAUUCUUAUAGGGGACCCUCCUCACCAUGAUCAUCAUGAUGAGUUUUGCCUUAUGCCUUGAAUCUUGAGGUUAAUAAUCAUAAAAUCCCUGCUUUCUAAAUUCGCAUUUUUCCUGGUGUACCUUUAAUGUGAACCUUUUGGCAUUCUUCUGCAAUUUUCUGAUUGGAGAUUGCAUUUUGACCUAGUCUGUAAGUUUUUCUGUCAGAAGAGGACUUUCAUCAACUUUCAUGGAAAGAUGUUUAUUGCAUACUGUAAAGUUAAUAAAGCAAUUUAAAAGCA